GGGGCCGCAAGCGGCAUGGAGGAGGCGGAGGCCGCGGCGAGCCGGGCCGAGCAGUGAGGGCCCUAGCGGGGCCCGAGCGGGGCCCGGGGCCCCUAAGCCGUGAGUGCCUCCGCGUGGGUGUCCGGAACGGGUAGCGCUGCCGGUGCAGGUCUCCUGAGCCCUCGGGCGGCUCCGGGCCCUGGGAGGAGGAGAGAAGCUGGGGCAGAUAGGAUGGGACGAGGGUUGAAGACUGGGGCAGGAGAGGUCGCUCUUUGCUCACCACAGGCUUGGGAAGGCCUGGAACUUGGUCCUUGUAGGGGCUAACGAACUUUGAGCCGAUUAUUUGGCCUCCACCCUUGGACAGCCUUGAUUCAGAGAGUUACUCCAGUCUCAGGGAAUUUCCAGAUUCCUGAAGUCAUGGGCUGGCCAGGACAUUGGUGACCCGCCAAUCCGGUAUGGACGACUGGAAGCCCAGCCCCCUCAUCAAGCCCUUUGGGGCUCGGAAGAAGCGGAGCUGGUACCUUACCUGGAAGUAUAAACUGACAAACCAGCGGGCCCUGCGGAGAUUCUGUCAGACAGGGGCCGUGCUUUUCCUGCUGGUGACUGUCAUUGUCAAUAUCAAGUUGAUCCUGGACACUCGGCGAGCCAUCAGUGAAGCCAAUGAAGACCCAGAGCCAGAGCAAGACUAUGAUGAGGCCCUAGGCCGCCUGGAGCCCCCACGGCGCAGAGGCAGUGGUCCCCGGCGGGUCCUGGACGUAGAGGUGUAUUCAAGUCGCAGCAAAGUAUAUGUGGCAGUGGAUGGCACCACGGUGCUGGAGGAUGAGGCCCGGGAGCAGGGCCGGGGCAUCCAUGUCAUUGUCCUCAACCAGGCCACGGGCCACGUGAUGGCAAAACGUGUGUUUGACACGUACUCACCUCAUGAGGAUGAGGCCAUGGUGCUAUUCCUCAACAUGGUAGCGCCCGGCCGAGUGCUCAUCUGCACUGUCAAGGAUGAGGGCUCCUUCCACCUCAAGGACACAGCCAAGGCUCUGCUGAGGAGCCUGGGCAGCCAGGCUGGCCCUGCCCUGGGCUGGAGGGACACAUGGGCCUUCGUGGGACGAAAAGGAGGUCCUGUCUUCGGGGAGAAACAUUCUAAAUCACCUGCCCUCUCUUCCUGGGGGGACCCAGUCCUGCUGAAGACAGAUGUGCCAUUGAGCUCAGCAGAAGAGGCAGAGUGCCACUGGGCAGACACAGAGCUGAACCGUCGCCGCCGGCGCUUCUGCAGCAAAGUUGAGGGCUAUGGAAGUGUAUGCAGCUGCAAGGACCCCACACCCAUCGAGUUCAGCCCUGACCCACUCCCAGACAACAAGGUCCUCAAUGUGCCUGUGGCUGUCAUUGCAGGGAACCGACCCAAUUACCUGUACAGGAUGCUGCGCUCUCUGCUUUCAGCCCAGGGGGUGUCUCCUCAGAUGAUAACAGUUUUCAUUGACGGCUACUAUGAGGAACCCAUGGAUGUGGUGGCACUGUUUGGUCUGAGGGGCAUCCAGCAUACUCCCAUCAGCAUCAAGAAUGCCCGCGUGUCUCAGCACUACAAGGCCAGCCUCACUGCCACUUUCAACCUGUUUCCGGAGGCCAAGUUUGCUGUGGUUCUGGAAGAGGACCUGGACAUUGCUGUGGAUUUUUUCAGUUUCCUGAGCCAAUCCAUCCACCUACUGGAGGAGGAUGACAGCCUGUACUGCAUCUCUGCCUGGAAUGACCAGGGGUAUGAACACACGGCUGAGGACCCAGCACUACUGUACCGUGUGGAGACCAUGCCUGGGCUGGGCUGGGUGCUCAGGAGGUCCUUGUACAAGGAGGAGCUUGAGCCCAAGUGGCCUACACCGGAAAAGCUCUGGGAUUGGGACAUGUGGAUGCGGAUGCCUGAACAACGCCGGGGCCGAGAGUGCAUCAUCCCUGACGUUUCCCGAUCCUACCACUUUGGCAUCGUCGGCCUCAACAUGAAUGGCUACUUUCACGAGGCCUACUUCAAGAAGCACAAGUUCAACACGGUUCCAGGUGUCCAGCUCAGGAAUGUGGACAGUCUGAAGAAAGAAGCUUAUGAAGUGGAAGUUCACAGGCUGCUCAGUGAGGCUGAGGUUCUGGACCACAGCAAGAACCCUUGUGAAGACUCUUUCCUGCCAGACACAGAGGGCCACACCUACGUGGCCUUUAUUCGAAUGGAGAAAGAUGAUGACUUCACCACCUGGACCCAGCUUGCCAAGUGCCUCCAUAUCUGGGACCUGGAUGUGCGUGGCAACCAUCGGGGCCUGUGGAGAUUGUUUCGGAAGAAGAACCACUUCCUGAUGGUGGGGGUCCCGGCUUCCCCCUACUCAGUGAAGAAGCCACCCUCAGUCACCCCAAUUUUCCUGGAGCCACCCCCAAAGGAGGAGGGAGCCCCAGGAGCCCCAGAACAGACAUGAGACCUCCUCCAGGACCCUGCGGGGCUGGGUACUGUGUACCCCCAGGCUGGCUAGCCCUUCCCUCCAUCCUGUAGGAUUUUGUAGAUGCUGGUAGGGGCUGGGGCUACCUUGUUUUUAACAUGAGACUUAAUUACUAACUCCAAGGGGAGGGUUCCCCUGCUCCAACACCCCGUUCCUGAGUUAAAAGUCUAUUUAUUUACUUCCUUGUUGGAGAAGGGCAGGAGAGUACCUGGGAAUCAUUACGAUCCCUAGCAGCUCAUCCUGCCCUUUGAAUACCCUCACUUUCCAGGCCUGGCUCAGAAUCUAACCUAUUUAUUGACUGUCCUGAGGGCCUUGAAAACAGGCCGAACCUGGAGGGCCUGGAUUUCUUUUUGGGCUGGAAUGCUGCCCUGAGGGUGGGGCUGGCUCUUACUCAGGAAACUGCUGUGCCCAACCCAUGGACAGGCCCAGCUGGGGCCCACAUGCUGACACAGACUCACUCAGAGACCCUUAGACACUGGACCAGGCCUCCUCUCAGCCUUCUCUUUGUCCAGAUUUCCAAAGCUGGAUAAGUUGGUCAUUGAUUAAAAAAGGAGAAGCCCUCUGGG